GCAGUAACCAUUAGUGCUGUGCUGGGGCGUGUUUGUCAGGAGGUUGUGCUUCAAAAGGUGGUAGAGAGAAGAAUGGAGGAACAAGGAAAGGUACAGUAAGCUGCAGAGUGCUGUGUAUCUGUCACUAUCGAGGGGAUGCCCUUUGCACCAUGAUUCUCACUUUAGUGGUGAGUUGAAUCUUGGCCUCAAGGCAUGUCAUGGAGCUGUGGCCACUGUGGAAACAACACCAGCAGACAGCUUAGCCUGUAUAUGGAUGGAGCGUCUCAGCAGGGAGAGGAACAGUUGAGCAUCUACCUUCACAAGAGGGCUGCUUUUCUACAUAGAGAGGACUGUUAGUCCAGCCUUAGGCUUUUCUGCUGUAUCUAAACAGAGCAGCCCAUUGGGGUCAUGUUUGAAAACAGCAACAACAGAGUAUCAAGUAGGUACAGAGGCUGAAUUCCCUGAAUUUCUGUGCAGAAGUUCACACCAGAGACCUGGACACUAGUUGGGGAGCUGGCCUGUGGAGACCAAGAGCUGCAACUUGAGAGUCAUGAGUUCUGAUUCGGGUCUGCACCUCUGCUUGGUUGAAGUGUUAAAUGUGUCCAGAAGACUGUGUUUUCUCCUCUUUUUUCUGUAAAAAGUGCGUGAAAUCUUGUCUGCUUGAUUUCUUGUAUGUCUUUUCGGGACCAGGGCAAGUACUUUUCGCAUGACUGACAUGGUAAGUAAAACCUGUAUGGAUCUUGGGAAGAGCUCUUGGUCUGAAUGAUUCAGUUUUUGCUAUUUUGCUGUUGAUUUGAUUAUUUAUGUGAGAAAGAUCUGUGCUGUUCCUGAAAAUUUGCUAAUAAAUCCAUUAAAAUAUCCCCCCCGCCGCCCCCCGUCAAAACACCCUAACAAGAAACUAUCCUAUUUUAGAGGGCACGUUUACUUUUUCCCAUCUCUUAUUUGAAAUGUUCUUUUCAACAUUCCCUGCUUUGCUUUUUUGAAUAUCAUGUUUUAGUUUUUUAUUUUUAUUUUGGUUCACUGUGGCUUUGGUUUAAUUACCCUUUUAAAUGGAAACAUGUAACUGCAGGCCCAGUCCAUCAUUUGUAUUAGUUUUCAGCACUCUGAACUUGGGUGGGUUGGGCACGAUUGUUUUAGUUGCUACCUGGAUAAGACUGUUGAGAUCUUAAUCUCAGAGUCUUGAAGAAUUCUGUUACUGAGGUAGCAGUGACUGUUUACUAAAGAAAAUAACCUUCAUUUUUUCUUCUUGACAGAGGUAAAAAUUCAGAGAAGAAUUUAAGAAGUCAGGGCAAUAAGAUUAAUUUAAACAGUUAUUUCUGUGUGUUUAGUAUUGUCACUAGACUUAAAAAGACAAUAAAAAUUUUAACUGAUAAAAUUACAAAUCAUCCUUGUUUUCCUCAUAGAGCAUAUCAAAUUCAGAAGAAAGAAGCUAUAAACUUUAUAUCUAGCAUGCAUUUUGACUUUUAAGAAAAUCAGUUAAACUCUGUAUCUCACCGUAUUCUCUCUACAGUAUAUUGAAAUAAAGCUAUAUGUUGAUUUGCUCAUUUCAUUAGGAUUAUUAUCCUGAUGUUUUAAAAGGUUUUUAAAGCUCCUGAAGCAAGAUGUUAUAAAAAUGCAAAAAACUUCAUAACCAAAAAAGUCUGGGAAAGUUAGUUUGUAUGCUAAUAACACCUCAUAUUUGCAUAGCUCUUUCAUCCCUGCAAGACCACCUUUAACAUCAGCUUAGUGGGCUCUCACAAUGCUCCCGUUCGGUGGACAUCAUCAGUGGCCUCCAUUUUGCAGGUGAAAAAGUUGAGGCCCAUGUAAAAUACACGUGGUCACACUAGACUUUGGCAAGGUUGGGCUUUGGACUCAGAUCUGCUGGUUACUCUCCAUGCCACUUGGGUACCUUCUCACAUUUUAUACGUGUAAAUUGGGAAGGUAGCAAUUCAUUUCUCUCUCACUUCAAAAAUGGAAACUCAGUAUCAUCAAAAGAUAAUCUUGGAGUGGCACUGUUUGAGGUGGUGAAUUGUUUGCUAGUUGAGAAACCAAAGAGUUGUUUUUCUUCUGUGAAAGGAACUGAAGUUUAACGCCUUGAUUGUGUGUUGCUGGCCCACUGUUACUUAGAAAAAUUAACUGCUCCACUGCUUAUUUUGAUAAGGCAGAGCAGCUGUUUGUCCUUGAAGUUUCAAAAAAUUAUAUUUAUGCACUAAAUUUAUUUGGCAAGUCAGACCUGUUUGUUCCAAUAAAGCAACAGUAUCUCCCCUGGCCAUUCUGGAAGCCACCUGUUGCUUUCAAGAGUUACAUGGAAGGGGCUGCUCCUGAGAUAUUAAAGACUCUUCAGAAUGUGGGGGCCACAUACUGGAGCCAUGUGACCCAGUGGGGAGCUGGUGCUGAUGAGGUCAAGGUCUCAGGCUGUCCUCCUUUGUGUAGGGAGCUUUGCAGAGAGCAGGACUCCACUCCAUAGUCCAAGUCUGCAUCCUCGACUUGGGCAGUGCCCACACAAAUGGGCAACUGUUGGCAAGGGCAUCUAUGUAUGUCCAUCCUGUCACCACCCCCUCACCGUCCUUAGCAUAUAGUCUUACCACUUGUGUCUUAGAGAAACCCUUUAGCCUUUGUCUUGAGACCUGUACACUGGUCCUCCUCUGUUAAUUAACAGGCAGGGAGCUGCCUCUCCUCCAGUUGUCCCUGUACUCUGGAUCGCAUCCUCUCCCUCCUGUGUCUUUAACUUCUCUGUCUGUGCCGUGUUUCCCCCAUCAGCCUGUAAGCAUUCUCACGUUCUAAAAAACAAGAAAGGUAGCAGUAGCCUCUCUCUAGCCUUCUCAGCUCUCUCUUCAGCUACCUCCUAAACUCUCUUCUCCCUGUUUUCAGCUGUAUCUAAAGAGUGUCUGUGAUCUCUUUCUGCAUUUGCUUUCCUUCCAUUCACCCCUCCACCCUGCCCCGCUUGUGAAGAUCAUCAGGGCUGUCUGUGCCACACAGUGAAUAGGUCUCCUUCUCUCAUUCCAUGCCUCAUUCUGGACAACUUGUUCCAUAGCCAUAGCUGCAGUUACCCAUGGAUUCACUGGUGACUCUCACAUUGAUGUUUCCAGCUCAGAUUUGCCCUCUGAGCCCAGACACUGCUGUCUGCUCUGCAUCCCCUCUAGCAUGCCCCCAGCCAUCUCACUACAAUGUAUUCACAUCCAACCUUCCCUGUCUUAUCCUGCCCCCUCCUCCUAUCUGGUCCUUUUCUGAAGUUAUUUAGUUUGGCAGAUGACACCACUAUCCAUUCUCCUUUAUGGCCAUUGAAUCGGACUGGAUGAAAGAGAGAGUAUUUUUUUUAAGGAGUUGGCAAGGUUAAGAAAUUACAGCAAGGUCUUCUUUCAUAAGAGAGUGCAUUUACCUUUUUGAAGAGAAAUGAUCAGUUCUGAUAGGGGCUGCUAUUAAAAUUAAACAAUUGCGUGAUUUCCAUGCAUUUACCUUUUUCUAAGAGAAAUGAUCAGUUCUGAUACAUGCUGCUAUUAAAAUUAAACAAGUGCAUGAUUUCUAUAGCAAGAACAUGGGCUGAACUGAAUUAAAGUGAUUUAACUCUUAAGUGUAACUUUCUCUCUAAAAUGCUUUGGGGCCAGGCACGGUGGCUCAUGCCUGUAAUCCCAGCACUUUAGGAUGCCAAGGCAGGUAGAUCACUGAAGGUCAGGGGUUUGAGACCAGCCUGGCCAACAUGGUGAAACCCUGUCUCUAUUAGAAAUACAAAAGUUAGCUGGGCAUGGUGAUGCGUGCCUGUAAUCCCAGCUACUCAGGAGGCUGAGGCAGGAGAAUCGCUUGAACCCAGGAGGCAGAGGUUAUAGUGAGCUGAGAUCAUGCCACUGCACUCCAGCCUGGUAAACAGAGCUACACUCCAUCUCAAAAAAAAAAAAAAAAAAAUGCAGUGCGUGUGUGUGUGUGUGUGUGUGUGUGUGUGBGCGCAUGUGCAUGCUUUGGAAGGAAUCAUACAAGUAUGUAGGUGUUAGUCUGCCUCUACCCUCAACCUUCAUUAAUCUUUGAGUCUCUUACCAUCAUUUGCCAUGCACUGGUUCAUUUGAAAUACAAAGCAAAUGUAAUUGGGAUCUGGCUCAGAAGCAUUUGUUUUUCGUAGGAAAGGUCUUAUAAGUUAGGAAUUGGGCAUAUUUGCAUGCCAGAGAGGGACGAUUUUUAAGUAUUUUGAAAAGGAGUAUUCAGGUGAAGCAAUUAUUUUCUUUUAAGGUUUAAUUUCAACUGUGAUCAUCUUUAGACUGGGAUAUCAGUUCUUAUCCUGGUAUCCAUGAUUAAUAAUUUUUUCCCAUUGACUUUUCUUGUUAUUUUGAAGUUUAUUUGAAAAAAAUUAUUUUUUAUGCCAAAGAUGUUACUAAGGUAUUUUGCUGCAGGCGAAUAUUGGGUAGGAUGCAUUGAUACUAUGCGUGGUCUGUAAGUUGCUAUGGGGGUGACUUUCAUGUUAUGGAACUGAUUUAGUUCCUGUUCGACAGGCACUGAAACAGGCCUGUCCUGCCAUGUGGUCACAGAUAUCUGUCUCUUAUAUUGGAAAAAUACUAAGAAAGCAAAGUACACUGGAGCUCCUGCCCUUAAAUUUUACUUUCAUUGCUCAAUAUGAUAAGGCACAAAAGCCCCUGUGCUGGUUUUACAGCAAGGUUCUUGCCAGUGAAAGUGUGGAAUCGGUAGGAGUUCUGAUGUGCCCAGCAGUGGGUGCUCAGAUGUAUGACAGGACAGAGCCCCAACGGUUCAGCAAAGUCAUGUGUUAUAUGGUCAAGUGGGAGAAGUCACACCUAACUGGAGAAACCCUGUGAAGCUUUAUUUUUGGGAAAUGAUCAGGUUGGUUUUGUGGCUGAGUGUAGAAGGAAAGGUUUGAAGCAGUUUCUGGAACAUGGUAUCAUACACACUCAAGGUUGCUGACAUUUCUUCUAAUAUUCUUAAGCAGGUUUUGGCAGACAGGUCCCUUCAGCCUGCACCUGGGUGAGCCCACUGGCAUUCUUCAUUACAAUCACAUGUUAGUUUUCGUUGAUUAUGUGCAUGUGGAGACUAUCAAAAAAAUUCAGCUUUUGUGAUCUUUUUUCAGAAGUACAGUGGCAAUGGAUAUCUUUGAACUCUAACAUUGUGAUGGUAAGAAAACUUUAGUCCUGUGAAGGAGGAGCACCUAGAUGUUGGGUAGCUAAUCUGGCUUUGCUGUUUUGGUGAAAAAAGUCCCAUGUGUUGUGGGAACUUGGAGCUUUCUACAUCCCUGCUUAGUUUUGUCAAGUCUGCUGGCCAGUAAUCCUGAAAAACAUUUGAUGCGUUGACUGCCCGCACAGUUGUCAAUUUGGCCAGAGUCAGAAACAUGAAUUUCACUCCUUAACCUUUUCAAGAGAUCUUGACAAAAAAAAAAAGCAAACUUUGGAGUUCAUUUUGUUAACACUUACGUUUACUGGUUUUCUAGAGAACCGGUUUGGGGUAUGUGUGUGUGGCGGGGGUGUGGAGAGAAUGCUUGUGUUUUAAAAAAGGGAAAACUGUUUUCACAGGGAGGAGUUUACUGGUGGGUUGGCUUAUUUGGUGGCUCUCAGCCCUUUGAAUGAGGCCUGUCUUUCAAUUCAAGGCUUUGCCAUCAACAUGAUGUGUAUGCUGCUGAAAAAGUAGGAAUGCUUUUACCCAGCUGCCAUCCUGGAAGCACAGCCUGGAAGCAGACAACCAAGUGCAUCUGCUGGCCAGUCAGGAAUUGAUAUGGUUUGGCUGUGUCCCCACCCAAAUUUCAUCUUGAAUUGUAGUUCCCGUAAUCCCUACAUGUCAUGGGAGGGACCUGGUGGGAGGUAAUUGAAUCAUGGGGGCGGUUACCUCCAUGCUGUUCUCAUGAUAGUGAGUGAGUUCUCAUGAGAUCUGAUGGUUUUAUAAGGGGCUUUCCCUCACCUUAGCUCUGUACUUCUCCUUGCUGCUGCCAUGUAAAGAAGAAUGUGUUUGCUUCCCCUUCUGCCAUGAUUGUAAGUUUCCUGAGGCCUUCCCAGCCCUGCAGAACUGUGAGUCAAUUAAACCUCUUUCUUUUAUGAAUUAUCUAGUCUCAGGUAUUUCUUCAUAGCAGCGUGGGAAAAGACUAAUACAGGAAUGGUACAGCUCUGGCAGUCUUUUUGCAAGCAGAAGCCUGUAUACUCCAGGAGAAACUAGAGAAUGCUUUUGAGGAUUAUUUUUGUUGUGACAGUCCCAUUAAAAUGUGGACUGAAUCCUCUCCUUCAUGACACAGACAGCAUCAGUGGUGCUGUCCUUGCCACAGAAGGCCCCAGGGUGUGUGGGCACAGCGAGUGAUGCAAGUGAUGUAACCAGAAGAGGUUUUGGGGGAUUUUCACACUUCUUUACACAUGCUAUCCUAGCCUGGCAGAGUGGUCUGUGAUUCCCCACUCAGUACUACCUCUCUGUCUUUUAUCCUUAAAAGAAAAACUGGAAGUCAAAGCUGAUUGGCUGUCAAACACCAGGCUCCAGUUUCAACCUCUGUAUCAAACCAAAAUAGCAGCCUUCUAAUGGAAAUUUUCUUUUAGUAUAAAAUGUACUUUCUUUUUUAUCUGUGCAAUUUACAUUCAUUUUAAUUUUUUGGAAAGCAGCCAGUUGAUUUUUGCAUUUAAAUGAGAGUGAGAAGUAUAAUUAUUUACACAAAUUUAAAAUUUUCUAUGUAAAGGAAAUAAAUUUCCAAUGAUGAAAUUGUAUACCAAAAAAUUAAUUGCAAAAUUUUGUAGGCAUGUGCAUAUGUUUCUGAGAGGUUUUCAUCAAAUUUUCAAAGGGAUCUGAAAUUAAACAAACAGCCAAACAACUGAUUCAGAGCAAGCUUCUGCUGUUGCAGCAGCUCUAGCUCACUGUUUAGACCUCCUCAGAAUAGCGACAGCAUACAGGGAGCCUAUUAGUUGUGUACCCCAAUCUUUGGUGAGCCUGGAGGGAGGUAAUUGAGAGGGAGGCAGGGGCCCUGAAAAUGGAGUAGGUGUUGAUGAGUGCCCAUAACUCUCCAGGCCCAGCCAGGGCACCAUUAACCAUCUUCUGCUUUGGCAAGAAUAAUCCAGAUCCACCUGGAGAGGCUUUUGGGCUAGGGAGGACUUUAUAUGCAGCAGGACUGCAUUAAUGACUUUCAGGCCCUUUUCCUUUGUAGGCUCCUUCCUCCAUAAAAAAAAAAAAUUGAAAAUUAUAUUUUAUGACUGUGUUGGUCAGAUCUGUUAAUAUUAUAUAUUAAAACGUUUUAUCUGAGCUAAAGGUCCUUUUUUCCCUUCUGAUUUUAAAAGAAAUUAAAACAUUUGUGUGAGCCCCUAAAAAUAUUGUGGGGCUGUAAGCAUUGUGCCUGUUGUACCCAGUGAAUAAGUUGGCCCUGAGGUGUGCAGAUCAUCUCUUGAUUUUUUUUCUAAAAUGUAUAAGGAAGAUGUGGAAUAUACAAGCGAAUAUGUUCUUUUUACUCUCAAUCUAUUAUUUUUGAAUAAAGUUGAGAGAAGGCAUUAAGCAUAUUAUUAAUUUACAUUUCAAAGAAACAAUUUUGAAUUCGUUAAUGUGGAACUUAUAUUUUUGAUAUAGAUUUCUUGUAUUGUUAAUUUUUGCAAAGAUAAUAAUUUUCAAAAUUUUAAUCAAAUUUCAGUUUUUAAAACUAAAAUUUUACUGUAUUAAUAUCAGUAAUGAAUAUUCUACAGAGUUUGAAAAGAUUUACUCUUCUGAGUGUAUUUGCAAUGAAAAAUAUUUUAAGCAUUCUUUCCAGUUUAUUUUGUGAAUAUAUGUAAUACUUUUUACAUAAUAAAUUAUUUUCUAAAAUAAAGCUUCAUAAAUUAGUUUUAUGUAAUAACUUGUAUGUCUUUUCCUGAUUCUGAGAAGUUUUCUAUGAAUUCUUUGAGUAAAAAUCUAUUUUAAAAGAUAACAGGCAAUAAUUUGUGACUAGGAAAUUUCAGAGUGGCCAGGAAAAACAUGCUAAAAAUAGAAACUGUUUGUUUACUCUGUGCUCCACCCAGUCUAAAACACAGCCAUGUGGUUGCAGACUUGGGGAAGGCCCUGUGGUAACUUGGAAGGUGUUUUUUCCCCGCUGAGUUGCAGAGUUUAAGAGAUCAUUCUUAUAACUUCUGAAUCCUGUUUCCUUUCUUUAGCAACUCAGAUAAAUUAUUUUUGCAAGCUGUUAUCUGAAAAUGAGUUUGACCAUGUUCGUUUAGUUUUUAGUGUCUUAUCAUCCUCCUUUCUACUUAUAUAUUUAAUUUAAGCCCUGUUUCAUGAAAGGAAAUUUUGAGAUUGGAGGUUUUACUAAUAACUUAUACCUCAAAAUUUGUCAGUUUAUAGUUUAAACUUUCCGGUGUUUUUCAUGAUAGUCUAAAAAAAUAGCCACUUAUUUGUUCAUUUUGUUACAAAAGGGGCUAGAUUAUGAAUUUAGUUCUUGGGUAGGCUUAUCACCUAGGAACAACACAACUUUAUAGGACUGAAUGUUAACCAGACAAGCCUGUGAUUUGUGUGCACAGAUAACAGAAACCAUAACCACCAGAAAGGCAGCCCAGUGAUACCAGUGUUGGGUCAGCCACACAUUUUAUUAGUCAGAUGCUUGGAGCACCUACCACUAUUCAGGACUCCUUGCCCAAAUGCUGUUGCUUUGUUAACUCUGUGCUAAGGUGUUAGGGCAUUAUGAUGCCCAGUUCCCCAGAGCACUCCAUUAGGGGCUUAGGCUUUGGAGUAAGCUGGCUGGUGUGAGUCAGACUGGGGGGUCACCUAUUGGCCUUAGUUUCCUUAUCUCUAAAAUGUAUAUAAUGAUGAGAUUAGUUUCAUUGGGUUUUUGAGAGAAUUAAUUGAAGUCAUGCAAGUAAAGCACAGCUUUCAAUAAUUAUUAGCAAUUUUUUUUUUGGUAUUAACGUACAGCAUAACAAAAGUCUAGAUUUACUUCAGGAGUUGUGCCCUUGAAGUAGAAUUUGGUUGUUUGCUUUACCUGCCUUCAUAAUGACUGCACGAAAGAAAUAAAUAUCAAUUCAUUUCAUUGUAUUCAAUUUGUUUUAUUUCAAAACAAGUUAAAUGAAUCUUUAAUUUUUUUUUAUUCCAAUGAUAUGUAUUCAUGUCAAUAUUUUAUUCCAGAUGAUGUUUAAGCAAAUAUAAGUGAAAAUACUGUGUGGGCUGAUUUGAUACUGUUUGUCAUUCCUAUUGUAUGUUUGACUCCCUACCUCCCUUUCGUGGGUUUUCUGUCUCUCUAUUUAAACUUUUUAUUAUGGGAAAUGGACACAAAUAGAGAGAAUAGUAUGAUAAACUCUUAUAUACCCAUCUCCCACCUUCAGCAGUUAUCAGCUCAUGGCUAAUAUUGUUUCCUCUGCAUUCCUAUCCACUUAUCCCCAUCCUGUGUUAUUUUAAAGCAAAUUCCAGACACCGUAUUAUCCAUAAACAUAUUUUUACCAUCCACAAUAUUAUUAUAUCUGUAAAAUAAUAAUAAUUCCUCAAUAUCAUCAACUAUCAACAGUGUUCCAAUUAUUUUUAAGAGGCAUAGCUUUAAAAAAAUUAGUUUGUUUAAUUUAGGGUCCAGUUAAGAUCCCAUACGUUUCAAUGGUUGACGUGUCUCUUUUUUCUUUUAAUGUACCCUAGUCAGUUCCUCAUUGUCUGUGGGCAGGAGGAUAUAACAUCCCUGGAUUAGCUGAGAGCUAUUAGUAGCUAACACUAAGGGCAGUUGCAGGGAUUUGGACAGGGCACCCACCACAUCCACUGCUUGGGGGAGGUGGUGGAUAAUCUUCAGGCACAGGGAACAGCAUAAGCCGGGACCCGUGAAUGCACAGCACAGCAUGUUUGGUGGAGUGACAAAGGUUGGCAGUCUGGGAGGUGGGCAGCUCAGGUUGGGGUGUUGGGGAUUGAGGCUGUGUUCCAGGUGGUUUAUUAUACAUUUUUGGUGCUGGGCUUAAAAAUAGCUUGUUUAUUCAGAUGAAGAUGAAAUUAAUAAAAGUGUGAUAUGAGUAGAGACUAUUGGAAAUAUAUAAUGUAUCAACAUACAUUUAUUUUCUGAAGAUGUGUAAUUUGGAAAAUUAUGGUAGUAUGUGAGAAGCAUCGUGACAUCUUAAGUUAACUAGAUAUCUGGAACAAAGUAUGCUUCAGCCUUCUUUCUAUUUUUUCCCGUAUUAUAAAAGUAGUGUUAGUAUAUGAUGACAUCCCAGAGGGCAGACCAUGGUUAUCAGUGUGUCUCAGGAGUAAUAUAGAAGAGCUUAUGUUAUCUGCCUGCUGCACAUAUGUAAAAGAAAUAUUUUGCUUAUUCAAGAGAGCAGUGUUUUAAUGUUUUUUCUAGUACAUUUAAAAUAUUUGAAAUUGUUAUCCUUGUUUUGAGUUUCAGUUCUUGGUGUGGUAACUUAAAAUGUACACUCUCAAUAUACAGGUUUUUGCUGUUACUUAAUAGCAAGGACCUGUGUUCAAAUUUUAGCUCUGCCACUUACUGUUUGUUGAGCAGAUUGCAUAUCUUCUUGUAGCUUCCUCAUCUAGGAAAAGGAAAUAAUAAUAGUGUUCCUACAGAGGACUGCUGUGCUGAUUAAAUGAGAGUGAAUCUAUUACAUUUAGCACAGGGUUUGGCACACCAAAGCACCCAAUGGUUUUAGAUAUCGCUAUUUUUACUAUUAGUGUUUUCUUAUUAAAUAUAUUUCAGGAUCAUUGAUUUAAGGUACACUAAGCAGAUAAUGACUAAGGUAUCAAGAGGAUUGGGAACAAGAAUAUUAACUUGUAUGUGUCCUGGGAUUGAAAUUUGCACACUGCAACCCAGAUAUUCUUUUAUUAAUAUAUUCUGUAACUUCCUUUCUAUUCUAUAACUGAUAUAAUAUUUCUCUGGAGUCCUAUUUCUGUUCAGCAAAAGCCAGAGAGAUAUCAAAAAUAAUUCUGUCUUUUUUGGUUUAAAACAACCUCCAUUAGCUUAAACGCCAUCUUUUUUGAAUAAUUCAGAAAUUUAAAGAUCGGGAUGGUUUCUUCCUACGUUAAAGGCUCUUCCCUUCCCAUUCCUAGGAAACAAUAUUGGUCUGACUGAUUACCAUUAUUGUUAUUUGGCUAUGGCCCACUAUGAUCACAUCACACACACAGAUUCUGCCUUCUGUCACCUUACCAAGAUGAACUCGCCUGGAUCCUGCCCAAAGCUGAUCUCUCCAUCCACACAAAAGAUCUCAAUCCUUCUUCCCUCCUCAGCUAAUUCAUAAGCAGCUCUCCCCACCUCUCCUGUAGCACCAGUUUUCACUCUCUACUGGAUUAUUCCCAUCAGCAUCAAACAUUCUGAGAUUUCUUUCAUAUUUUCUUGUUGCAACUUCUCCUGCUGGCUACUGCACAAUUUCUUUGCCCCCUUUGCAGCAAAAACAAUUUGAAGAGUUGUCAGUGCUCACUGUCUUCAAUUCCUUGCUCCUGUUUUUUUUUAAAGCUGCUCCCUUCAGGUCCUCACUGUCACUUUUCUCCAAAGCCACUCUUGUCAAGGUCACCAAUACCCUCCAAGUUCCUAAAUCCCUCAAGUCAGUUUGCAGUCCUCCCCUUACUUCACCCGUCAGUAGUGUUUGGCAUGGCUGAUCAUUCCCCUUCUUGGCACACUUACUUCGCUUGGCUUCCAGGGCUCCCUACUCUCCCAGUUCUCCUCCUGUCUCACGCAUCAGUCUUUUCAGUCCCCUUUUCUGUUUGCUUCUCUUCUGUUUGCUUGCAGCAUUGGAGUGAUCCCAGCCUUCUUUCUAUCUGUUCACACUAUCCUGAUAUUCUCAUCCCGUCUUGUGGCUUUAAGUGUCAUUUAUAUGCCAACCACUCCCAAAUAUACAUCUCUACCCCGACUCUCUUCUAUGAUCCAAGCAUAUAUGUCCUACUAGAUUUUUCCACUAUAUCCUACUAGAUCUUUCACUUUUCAUAUCUGAAACACAACCCCCCCUUUUCCCCACCCAGCCUGCUCCAUCUGUAGCCUUCUUUCUUAGUUUGAUAAUAUCCUUUCAGUUGCUCAGGCCUUGGAGUCAUCCUUGACUCCUUUCUUAUCUCAUGUACUACAUCAAGUCUAUCAACAAACACUUUGGUUUUAUCUUCGAGAUAUAACUAGUGAUAGUGUGCUGUAAGUAUUAUUCCCAAUGUAGAAUUUGUAAUGGGGCCAGGCACGGUGGCUCACCCUGUAAUCCCAGCACUUUGGGAGGCGAAGGUGGGUGGAUCACUUGAGGCCAGGAGUUCGAGACCAACCUGGCCAACAUGGUGAAACCCCAUCUCAACCCAAAAUACAAAAAUUAGCUGGGCGUGGUGGCAUGUGCCUAUAAUCCCAGCUACUCCGGAGGCUGAGGCAGGAGAAUCACUUGAACCCGGGGGGCGGAGGUUGUAGUGAGCCGAGAUAGCGCCACUGUAUUCCAGCCUGGGCCACAGAGCAAGACUCUGUCUCAAAAAAAAAAAAAAAAAAAAAGUAAUGAGCACAGCUCUGAUUUGAAUACAGGUCUGUCAGGCUCCAAAGUUUUCUCCAUAGUUUUGCAUUAAUAUAUUCUUAAUUUUAUAUUUGCAAAGUUAUUUUUAUUUUAAUAUCAUAGCUUAGUGGGAGAGUAGGGACACUAUUUAAAACUAAGGAGCAGACAAAGAAUACUCCAGAGUAUCUUUAGAAUUUACUUAGUUUGUCUCCCUAGUUCUAGGAAAUCUGAAUCUAACUCAUAUAUUAGAUUAUAUUUUCUUUGGAACAAACCCAGAUCUUUAAGAAAGAGGAGUUCAGUGCCUCCUUUCCCAAUUAGCUAAUCAUCUAUAAGCUUCACUUUUGUCAUACAAAGGUGCUGGACUCCCAGAGUUCAUGCAGUCACAACUCAAAUGGUGAAGAGGAAACCUGAACUGUCUCUAGUUAUUUUUAGGUGUUCCUGAUAAUCAAUUUUCAUGCAAAAUACAAAUGAUCAUUUAUUUGUCCCUUUGUUUUCAUGAAUACAGGCUGAGCAUCUGUAAUUCAAAUAUCCAAAAUGUUCCAAAAUCUGAAACUUUUUGGGUACCAACAUGAUACCACAAGUGGAAAAUUCCAUACCCUAACAGCACCUUUGCUUUCAGUGUACAUAAACUUUGUUUCGUACACAAAAUUAUUAACAAUAUUGUAUAAAAUUACCUUCAGGCUAUAUGUAUAAGAUGUAUAUGAAACAUAAAUGAAUUUCUUGUAUAGACUUGGAUUCUAUCCCUAAGAUGUCUCAUUAGGUAUAUGCAAAUAUUCCAAAAUCCCAAAAAAAUCUGAAACGCUUCUGGUUCCAAGCAUUCCAGAGAAGGGAUACUUAAUAUGUAGUAGUAUAUGGAUGCCUUGCCUCAUAGUCACCCUCCCCAGUGGUUUAAUGCAACCAUUAAAUUAUUUUUGUUUUAAAAUAUUUGAUCUGGGUUUGAAUUUAUGGAAAUACUUCACGUCAGUUUUUUUUUUUAAAUAGCCAAAUAGUGUUUCAAAAUUUUAUCAAGAUUGUGAUUGGUCUUUAACCUUAGAAGCAAAACUGACAUGGAAGGAUGAAACAAGUAGGUAGAAUGGUGAAUUUUGGUAUUCAUGUGUUUGGACAUCUGUGUCCUUAUCAAAAGAAAGAAUGUAUAUAGUUGGACAAAAUUGAAGGUCCAUGUGGUAUAUUUAGAAAAUAUUACUUGUUAGUGGUUUAACAUGUGUAUAGUGGUUUUACUUCAAGCACUUUCAAAGAUUUGAGUUUGUUUCUGCCCUUGUAACACUUCAACAGUCAUAUUAGUUUGCUUUACCAUUUUUCUUUGAAGGGAACUGAGACUGAUUCAGUUGUGCAAGGUGAUGAGCAACAUUGCUCAAAAAGCCAGAAAUAGAUUUGUGGGCUUCUGACUGUGAGACCAGGUGCUCUCUCCACUGAAUUAUUCUGCUUUCUUUGACUGUUUUCUUUGCUUUAAAAAAUAUUAAUGCACAAUUCUGAAUUGCUGUUGACUGUGAGAUAAAUUCAUGUUAGAUCUAUAAAUAAUGCACUUUCCAACCAAACCAGCCAAUGGAACAAAACGCUUUUUGAGACAUUGGUGUUGGAAGAUGGCCUCCUCCCACCAGCUGACUGUAUUCUCAUCAUCCCCCACAUCUGUCCCAUUGUUUCUGAUGCUGGUACCAGGCUCCUGUCUCCAACACAUGCUUAGAUAAUUACAAGAAUUAACCUCCCUUCCUUCUGUUCUUCUCCCUUUCCCCCAAAUCCUUUUUCACAGUUUCCAGAUUAGUUCUCCUACAGCACUACUUUGUGAAAUUCUCUCAACAUGUUCUAUGAUACCCUUUGCUCUGAGGCUGAAGCCCUAACCUUCCUCUUGGUUUCCAGGACCUCCCAUGUAUCAUCAGUACUACUCUAGCAUCUUCUUCUGCUUCUCACCAACCUCCGUCUUGGCCAGACUGGGCCUCGCAAACUGACAUUACUUCACCUCUCUUGUAGUCUUGUAAUCUGUACCCUAUUCCAGAAUUACUCUCCCUCUCCUUUUGGUUAGCAAGCCCAGCUUUCCUCUAGGGACUUUUCUUACCCAUUCGCUGGAAAUUUGGUUGUAGGUGUGCCCUGUAUCUUUUAUCUAGUAAGACUCUUCUGUGGGUUUACUAAUUUUCAUUUAGAAAGAGGAUCACUACCUAAUGAUGUAAGGUGUGGUGUAAAAUUUUUCUCAAUUAUAUUUUCAGAUUAUUGCUGGGAUUCUGUUAUGAUUAGUAAGCAAACGAAUUAAUAUUUUAAUGGUUGACUGCCUUCUGAUAUGUUUACCUCAAAUUAUAUCAUUUUAAAUUAUAGAUUUAAAUUUUAAGAAAAACAAAUAUUUACAUUUAGUCAAAGAUUUUGUGAAAUGACCUUGUUUUGAGAAAGAGAAAUGAAGUCCAAUUACUGAAUAGAAUAUGAAUAUAUAAAUAUAUUUAUGUAUGUGUAUAUAUGUAAAAAAUAGCUGUCAUGUAGUCAUUAUUUUUGUGACAGUGUAUUGCUAAAAAGAUCUUCAUAAUAAUUUUGAAUAGAACACUGGGGGUGCUAGAUUUAGAAAUUAAUGAUUUUAUGGAAGAAAGAUCUGCCUGUAAAUUUUGCUCCUAUUAUGAAUAAAAGGGAGACCCUUAUUUCAGAUUAUCGAAAUACAGGGACUGUAGCAUUAAUGUAACACCCACUAUAAUGUGUUUCUUUUAAAAAUGUUUUCUUCAACACCCUGUGAUAUAUGACUUGCCAGAUUCUCUGAUCCUGGGGCCCUUUAGCAGCCAUGCUAUGUGUUGUCAUAAUGUUUUAAAUUUGUGGCUCUAAAAUGCAAUUCAGUUGUGUUUAGCCAGUGUUGAUCUUUUUCUUUCUUCUUAAUUUGGGACUUUCAGUGUAUGCCAUUACUUAUGAGAAGUGCUUUAGUUAUGAGUUGUGGAGAGAGAAAGUAGUUGGAGAGAAAAUUAAGGUAACUCUAACAUAGAUCUUAAUAUAGUCUAUAAAGUUUUCAUGAGGAUAAUACAGUGAGUUUUAUAUGUGGAGAAAUAUAUAGAACAGUGAGUGGAGGAAUUAGGGAGCAACAUAUUCAAUUUAAUUGUCUUAAACACUAAUAUGAUCUAAGAGAAAGAUCAUAAGAAAGUUGUCAAGUUUUCUAAAAGAAAGAAAGUUUUCAAAAGAUGUAUUUCUCAAAUUCAUCUGUCAUUAAAAUUAGUAUGUUGAAUUGGAUUCUCAGCUUAUAAAUUAAAAUAUAAGUGUUCUUACAUGAUAAACUGAAUUUAAAUUUCCAGGUUUUUUUUUUUCUCUUGGUGGUCCAAUUUCAUUGUAUUAAAAUAUGUAGGUAUCUAUCUUUUUGCGUAGAUUUGGUAAACUUUGGUUUUCAUGAAGUUAAAAUGAAUGAUUAAAAAUUUGUAUAGAAUUUGUUAGCGUCUUCUUGUUACAGGAUUUAGGGGGUAUGUGUGAUUUAAAGAUUAAUUCAUAAAAUAUUUCUUUAUUUAUUUUAUGUAUUUUUUAUUGUUUUUAGAGACAGGGUCUCACUCUGUCACCCAGGCUGGAGUGCAGUGGCAUGAACAUAGCAGCCUCAGCCUCCUAGACUCAAGUGACCCUCCCUCCUCAGCCUCCUGAGUUGCUGAGACAUACAGUCAAAUGCCACAAUGUCCAGCUAAUUUUUAAAUUUUUCUGUAGACAAGAGAUCUUGCAGUGUUGCCCAGGCUGGUCUUGAACACCUAUCCUCAAGUGAUCCUUCCACCUCAGCUACCCAAAGUGCUGGGAUUAUAGGCAUGAGCCACUGCCUCUGGCCUAAAAUAUUUGUAUAAAUUGAAAGACAAUACUUUUGAGUUUAAGGAAAUGAAGAUUUGAUCUGCUUUAAAGCUGUCUUAGUAGACGGAUGUUGGAACAAAUCAAUUAAAACAUAUCUUUUAUAAUGUGGUAAAACAAAAUUAACAUAAGCUGAGCAAUGCAUAACAUUAGUGAACAUUCUUCUCGCUAUGAGGUUCAUGCUUUUGAUAAAGGUCUAGAAGUUGCUUCAGACGUCAUUGAAAUUUUUAUAUUUAUUCUCACCUUGCCUAUUUAUUUAUUUACCUUGCAGUCUUUUUUAUUUUUAAGGUGAGAGAUUCUGGGUACUAAUAUACACACAUUCACUGUACACUGAUAUUUAGCCAAACCAUGAAAUAGAAAAAGCUGGCAUAUAUUUACUGUUAGAAUCUUUGAAAUUUUUCAGUGUAUAUUUCCUGUUAUAGUUAUUCAUGCUCCAUAAUUCAUGGGUUUUCUUGGCACUGGCAACAGUUACUUCCCUGUGGUUUAGAUAUAUUUUUUUGUAGUAUAGGUAGGUUUCUUUGCUGCUCUCAUAUUUUUCCUUUUAAUUUUAUUAUUUUUUUCCUCUUCUUAUUCAGAUAGUGUUUCAUCUCUGUCAUUAGGAAACUACUUCUCAUUGAUUUAUUCUGUUUAUGCAGUUUUUCCUUCCAAAUUCAUCAACUGAACUAUGGGAAACUUUGUUUCUUAAAAGGUUAUUUUGACAUUAUUUGGGUCAGGCCAGGUUUCACAUAGGGAAAAGGACAAUGCUUCUGCUUUGCCUUCCCAUCCACCACUAACAGCUUUGUGAAAGGAGAGAGAAGUAGAAGGAAAGGAUAGAGAGAGAAGGAGGGACGCCUCAUUCAGCUUACAUUUCAGAAGCAGGGAAUGCAAUAAAUAACAUGAAGAAAGUCCAGGCUCAACUCGCUCACACCUCAGGAGGUGAUUCACGAGCAUGUAACACAGCCUGCUAAGGUUUCCAUUAUUCAUAAUUAAUUAAAUCAAAGCAUGCUUAGUAAGGGCCCAUAAUCUUAAAAAGCAUUCUGUGUUUUCAUCUGACUAAAAGUUUUUCCUUCGCUUGUUGCAGACGACAGCCGACUUUAAUAUUAUAGCACCAGCACGGUACAGUUGACUCAGUAAACCUGCCACACUGUGGAACAGAGGUUUGGGGAAGAAUGUGGAAUGUGAAAUAUAAGACUAUUCAGCCCCUUAAAACAAUGACUAUCCAAAUAUGUUGCUUUUGAGCUGGUAGUUUCUCACUUAUUUUGUUUAAAAAAAUAUAACAUCCUUUGUUGGGUUAUAGGUUUCACUGAGGCAGAUGGGUUUCUGUAGUGAAUUAGUCCCUGCAUCUACUGAGAGUAUCCUCCCUCCAGCAUUAAAGAAGGAAAAUAAGAAAAUGGCCCAUAGCAUAGAGGAAUGGUCAGGUGGGAAGUAGCUUCUCCUUAAAUUAUUUCUGAUGGAAAAAAUAUAUUCUGGAGCUUGGCAUUUGAGUUCAAUAUUGCCAAAACUCCAGGAAUAACUUUCUGCCAAGAGCACCCAGUAUGUCAAAGAAAAUAUUCUAAAAGAAGUAAAUUAAUACCAUCCAUGUAAAGAAUCAGUGGCAUUGUGGCAUCAAAUGAGUGUGCUUCAUAUAAUGCUAUGAUCUUUUUAAUUAAGAGGAAAAGUCCAAAUAAUUGAUGAUGAACAUUUACAAUUACUUUGAUAUCAAUUACUUAAAGAGACCUAAACCAUAAAUAUAUUACAGAAUUUUGAAAGAUAAAAGAUAAAGAUAGUUAAAAUCCUUGAUUUUUCCUCUUUGGUAUUCAAGGCUGUAUGGUUACUUAUAUCUUUGGCUUCCUUCUCUCUUUUGUGAUCGUACAUUAUCCAUGUGUCAUCCUGUACCUCAAAGGGUGGAGGAACAACUUAUGUGUUCUUUAUCUCCCCACCUCCCCUUGCCUGUGUUCUUUGUCGUACGAGCCCCUGGGAGACUCAUAGUUUCCUCAGUAGGUUGCCUGGCAGUAACUGGAGAAUGAGAUAGCUAUGCUAUAAAAGGCUCUUCCUUCCCUGGCCCAGCCUUUUCCUGGUACUUAGCCCCUUUCUGUCCUUCACAUCCGGAUGUACAUAGGACACGGUCCCAUUUUGUUAAGGACACACAUCCUCUGUGUAACAGUGUAUUCCUCUUCCUUUCAAUUAGAGUCAUGUCUGAAGGAUCUUUUUAGCUUUCUGGGCUAUCUGGUUACCUAACCAAUAAAUUAGAAUAAUUAGUCCUAUUACUAGGUUCAGCAGUAAUGUAGAGUCUUAACAGCUUUUGUUUUAGGUCAAAACAUGCUCAUUUGGUUACCUACAAACUAUAUAACAAACCACCUCAAACUUAGUGGCAUAGAACAGUGACCAUUUUAUUAUGAUCAUGAAUUCUGUGGGUUGACAGUUUGAACAGGACACAUCAGAAAUGUCUUGUCUCUGCUCUCUGAUGUCUGGGGCUUCAACUAGCUGUGGGGAUUCUGAUGACUAGAAGCUGGAGGGUUCACUUCCAGGAUGGCUUCCAUACUCACAUGUUGGGUACCUUUGCAGGGAUAGCAGGACUGUUGGGCUCAGCUGAGAGUGUCAGCCAGAGUGUCUAUGUGUAGCCUCUCCACUCAUGAUAGUUCCAGAUAGUUGGAUGUUCCCCAGAGUAAGCCUCCCAGGAGAACUAGAUAAAAGCUGCAUGGCCUCUUCUGACCUAAGCUUAGAAGUUACACUGAGUCACUUUGACUGCAUUCUUUUAGUUACAAGUGAUUCAUAGACCAGCACUGAUUCAGAGAGAUGGAAAUGAGACCCCACUCCUUGGUGGGGGAGUGGCAGGUGCACACUGAAGAGGAUCAUGUAGGAUGCAAUAUUGUGGUGGUCAUCUUGGGAACUUAUGCAAAAGGGAAACUCAGUCAUCUUGAUGUUUUGAUUCCAUAAUGCCAGACUUCUAUUUUCUUAUGUGAAUCAUUCAAAUGUCUCAUUAUUUGAAAAUUUGAUAUUAUGUAGAAAAAAUUUGGAUGAGUACGUGAAUAUCCCCCUUUUUACCUAUGUAUAUUACCAUCUGACAGAUAACUUUUGCAUGACUGAAUCAAAGGAGCACUGUUCAACACAGUCUUGGUUCAUACCCUUAAUCUGAGAAACUAAAGUAAGGCUGUAAGAUUGUGCCAGGUUAUUAUAAGGAAGAACAGAUUAUCACUGUGAACUUUACAGUCAGCAAGGCAUUUAAACCAGGAAGACAAAAGGAGAGAGAUGUUAAAACAAUAGAUAGUUUUUGUGCUUUAUAUGAAAAUCUCAUUUUUUAAGUAGCUGGUUAUUGAAAAAUUAUAUAUUUAUGACAGAGAAGACUUUAACUAUUAAUCACAAAAUUCAAUUUGUGUCUCAGUGAUAAAGCGAUUUCCUCCUUUUCUCCUAUUUAUGAUAGAUUUUUAUGUAUGAAAAUGCAAUUAAUUUCAAAGAAUAAUAGGUGAGUCUGGGAACCAAAUAGGAAAAUAGUCUCUUUAUGCAAUGUAUGGAAAGUCCCCUAAUGUUAAUGGCUAUACUGGCUCUAAAUAGUAUGCCACAGAGAGAUGCAUUUUGGGGUUUGAACAAUAGCUUCAUAUUACCGUAAUAGUUAAGGUGAUGGGAAAGAAUUAUGUUCCACAGGAUGUAGAAUUACCAUAACUUUAUGUGUUGAAGGAAAAAGGCUAAGCCAGUAUAAUGACCUGGGCAAGGACUUGACUUUGCUGGGUCUCAGUUUCUUCAUCUAUAAAGGGCUGAAACCUCACCUAGUUAUAUAAUUCUUUGAUUUUGUUGCUCUUUGUGCUCACAUAGCACUGGAAUAAAGCAGUCAAAGUUAAUGUUAAAUAUAGGAGUACAAAGGUCAUUCAGCUAAGUUUCAGAAAGUUAAUAAAUCCUAAUCACUUUACACUUGACAGCAUGUAUAAACUUGUAUCCACUAAUCCCAAAAGUUAAAUAGAAGUACUUCAGGAAAACUCUGGAUUAAAUAAAUUAUUUAAAAAUAUAUGGACAUCAUUCUUAAACUUAGAGCAGUUGUUAACCAUAAUACUUCGUUGUGAAAUAGUUUAAUUAAAAUUUUUAGUUUUAUUUGUUUGAACCAAAAAACUGAAUUCACUCAUUUGGAGCCAAAAUUUAAAUUACUAAAUAAUAAUUUAAUAGGAAAUAGUACAGUUGAAUUUCUGAAACUUGUUCUUCUGAGUUUAAUAGUGCCUUUAUAUACUAGCUAGUUUGAAGUCUAGGCACUGCAUUAUUUUUGUACUAUUUAGUUAUAAGGUAUUAGGAAUUUGUCCAUUUCGCCUACAUUUUCAAAUUUAUUAGCAUAAUGUUCAUCAAAUUAUCUCGCCUUUUUACAACCCACUGCAUAUGUAGUUUUGUUCCUCUUUUCCUUACUAGAAUUGUUUGUCCUUUUUUACUGAUCAGGUAUGCCAGAGAUUUAUCAGUUUCAUAAUCUUUUUAAGCAUUAAUUUGUGGCUUUGUUGAUUUUAUGUAUUGUUCUAUUGUAUCCCUUUUCGGUUUCAUUAAUUUCUGAUGUUAUCUUUAUUAUUUCCAUUAUCCUUAUUUCUUUACUUUUUCUUUCUUUGGGUUUAUUCUUUUUGCUAUUUUUCUGACUUUUAAAGUUGUGUGCUUAGCUCUUUAAUAUUUAGCCUUCCACUAGCUUGUGAAUUCUGCAGCCUAUAUAGUUGGCCUACAGAAAAAGUAUACUCCUUAUGACUGGCCUUUUUUGGAGUCUGGUUGAGGGGACACCUGUUUUCUUGGAGGUGCUUCCCUCAAAGUGAGGAAGAGUCACCUGAGGUAUUGGCACAUGCAUAAGUGUUCUUCUUGGGAAUCCUCAUUGCAAAGAUUCUGUGAACAUGGACUUCUGAAAUGGUAUUUUCUGUAAGCUGUGGGGUCAGAAUUAACAAAGCAAUUGAAAAUUCACUCAGGCAAAUUAUAGAAUAAUGAAUAUCCAUAUAUAUACCACAUAUAUGGCAUCUGUCUAAAACUUAAUCACCAGAGUAUAAUCUUGUCAACCCCAAUUUUAUUUUCCUGACUGCCUCUGAGAGUAGAAAUCAGUGAGGCAAAUAUCCUGUGUGUUUUUACACAAAUUGAAAUUAUUUUUCCAUAAUAUUUUGUUAAUGGUACUGUUUGUGUUUGUAGUUGAGUUACUUUGACCUCUGAAGCAUCUUCCACACUGUUGCAUGUAAAUGGAACAAUAGGUACUUGAGUCACUUGAUCAUGGAUUCCAGAUUCUGGAACAGCCUCUUUAGAAGGCAACAGAGGAUAUUAUUUACUGAUUUGAGUGGCUUUAGAAUAUCAUUUAACUUUUUAAAAUUAUAUUUAUUAGAUAUGAUCUUAAUCUUUAUAUAUUUUUCUUUUAUAGAUGAUAUAAUAAGGCAUUAUUAGUAUUGUAUAAUUCUCAAGGGUAUUCCACAUAAAUAUUUAAAGUUAAUUUAUAAAAGUUAAUUUUAUUGCUUACUAUGAUUAUAUGAUAAAUUCUCACUUAUUGAGAAUCUGAACUGGAAAGGUCAACCAAAAAUUUAAAAGCAGAUAUAUAAAUUAGGGCGAGAGAUAACGAGAGCAAGUGCUUUGAGCCCUGUGAGUGGCUAUUACACACUAGCAUGGCUAUUGAUGAGGAUGGAGAGGGCCUUUAGGGAGGGCAUACUUAAAGAAUGCAGGAGUGAAAAUGCUUGUAUGGUGUUUUAAUUCAUUUUAAAACUAUAUUUUCUUCUCAUUUAACCAUAGGCCACUCAGUUCCUCAAAUACUGUGAAUAAAUAGGAUUUUAUUGGAUUGAUAACCACUGUAUUACAACCACUACUACGUGAGAAUACAAGAAAACAGUUUGAAUACUAAUUUCUCGCACCAAAUCAUAAUCUAUAAAUGUGUUUUGGUAAUUCCACAUUUAUAGCUUUCCUUUAUUUUUGUCCUUUAAAGGAAGUUUGGUGUGGUAAUGGCCAUUAAAAUUAUUUCUCAUUUCAAUGAAAGUUUGAAUUAGGAAUUUUAUGCAGAUGAACAAAACAGAUUAAGGCCAUUUUUUGAAAAGGUGCUUAACAUUUUGACUGAAAAGCAUCUUUAAACAUUACAAGUUUUAUUUUAUUUGUGGGCCUAGCUCAUAUGGUAAGUUUUCCUAAGGGCAUGGAGCAAAGCUCUCAGCUUCUUAAGUGUGUUUAUAGCAACAAAUACAUGCUACAUGGUAGGGAGAGAGCUAGUCAGAUAUUUUAGUCAUAUAUUUUUAAAAUGGACUGUUCCAGAAUAAGGUUGCCUUUGAAAAGAGUCUUUCAAAUAAUUAGUGUCAAGUAGAUUAUUUUAGUUUUAAUUUAAUCAUCUGUUUCAUCAUAUAAGAAAGCUUUCAAUAUCGUGACCAAGGGAUUGGGGCGGUCUGAUGUAUUGGAAAUGUGACUUACUUGCUCCAGACACUUUGAGAAAGUGUGAAUUGGUGAAUCUCACAUCCAUUCUUGGCAAGCUGAUAGAGUAUCUAGGAAAGGGUAAGAUUAUUGAACACAUGAGCUGAGAAUAAUCUUUUGAGGAAAACAGUAUCUGGAUUUUCCUAAAAGGGGAUCUUAUUUCAACAGACCUUCAGCAUUCUUCAAAAGCUAGGUGAGGAUGUGAAUGAGAAAAACAGGAGAUGUACUGCUCCCUGUAUAUUGCAACAAUGUGAAAUAGAAGUAUGGCAGACUUUGAGGGAACAAGAUUCUAAAUUCCCAGAAUAUCACUAAUUUAUUUUCAUAUACCAGUGCAGAAUUUUUUUCUGAAGACAGGUGUAAAUCAUUUUAACAUGAUCUUUAUAACCACCACCUUUCUAUUAAUCAGGCAAUCAUCAAGAAAGAAUUUGAUUGUGAAGGGUCCAGAUUGAACUGUUCUUUAAGUAAGGACACAGGAAAUAUUAAGAUAACUGUAUGGAAAAAUCUCAUCCAAGAAACUGGAAGCUAUGGGAAAAAGAAAAUUAAAGAUUCUUUGAUUUUAGUAGGUUGGUUGAGUUAUACAUAUUUUUAGCAGAGCAAAAAAAGAGAGAAAAAAGUUGCAUGCAACUAUUUAAAAAGAAUGUGAUACAACAAAAGCUAUUUUUAAUCUAUGUCAGGGUAGGAGGAAAAUUUAUACUUUUUAAUAGUUAUGAACUUUUAAAAUUCGUAUGAAGCAGAAUCUUUACUGCUAGAAGAAUUUGGCUCUGCAGUUUUUGUUAUGUUAAAACUUAUUCAGGAAGAAUUUCAGUAUUCAGAAUUCAGCACUCUGAUUUAGAGUUUUAAUAGGAAUGCUAAGUCAAACCUAUUUUAAGCAUAUUACCUCCCUCAAAGCUUUAAAACAAUUCUGAAAUUUUAUAAAGGUCUAAAAUUGGUAACUUUAAAGAUUUAAAAUCACUUCAUGCUUUUCUAACUGGAUGGAACUUUCUUUGAUGCAUUGUGUCUCAACUCUCAUGAAAGAUUACUUCCUUUCUCAAAAGAAAUCAUUCCUAAGAUCUCGUAAUUCCACCAUAUAUAGCUAUGGAGGAGGCCAAAUUAGGGAAAUAUGUCUUCCUAUGCAUGUAUGCAUUUGUACUCUUCCUAUGCAUGUAUGCAUUUAUACUCUUCCUAUGCAUGUAUGCAUUUUUAACAGAGGGCUUAGAAACAAUAUUAGGUGCUGUUGAAGAUAUCCUGUAUGGGAUAUUUCUGUCAGUAUUGUACCAAAUAUCAUAAUUGGGAAUGAGCAAAUGAAACUCUACCUGUGAAUGGGCAUAGAAUACUUUCCUAGCCCAUAGUAAUAAAAAUAAAAAUAUUAUUAAGAAAAAAUAUAUUAAGAAAAAAAUAAUGUUAGAGACAGCUAAAUAUACCACCUCAAAAGAGGGUAAAGUACAGGGUUUAAUAAAAGACAACCCUUCCCUCACCCACCCUCCAUCAAGGCAUCCAUUAAUACCUUGGAGAAACAGAAAAGCUUCUGAAGGCAAAAUAGUGCAUAUGAAACCUUGAUUUCCCUAUCAAUACUUACUGUAAAGGUGAAAAAAAGGAUUCAUUUGAGAAAACAAUAACCCCUCUAUAAUACAUAUUUAAAAUAUAGCAACCUCUUUCUAAGAAUGAAUUUAAAAGAUCACUAAGUAUAAUAAAAUAUUUUUAAGUGUCAAAAUAAGCUCGGCUCCCCCACAACCACCAACCAGCCAUUAAAAUGUGAUUUGUGUUGGAAUACCUGACCAGAGUGACUCAGACUCUACAACAUCUAGGGUAGGGGUCUCAGUCUUUUGUCUCCUGUUGGAGGGAUAAGGGAGAGCUCAGUCCAUAACAGUGGCUGUUCACCACCCUGGUGAUUUGAGAGUGGAGGUGGGGGCAGGCAGCUGGUUAGCUGGAGGGCAGGUAUCACAUCAGGUGAUCUAGCAGUGAGGAGAGGGGAAGACGAGGGAGGUUGCAGCACAGCUGCAAAAGGAGCAAGAGAGCAAUGACAGCAGAAGGCUGAAGACCAGUGAGAGUGGCCAGGGUUGCACAGGCAGAGGCUUGGAUUUCUGCCUGCCAUUUCCUCUUGCCCUCUUCAGGGUCUUUAGCACAGCGCCCACCUCUCAAUGGACUUUUAUUGAUAAGGAAUUCUAUUCUUUCAGACUUUCACUCUUCUUGUGUCAGAAACACCUGGGGGCAUGGGGCUUGGUUCAUUUGACCUUCAUACACUCACAUAACCACUUCUGUUAGUACCACCCUUAAUUAAACAUUAUUUUUCAUUUGUCAUCAGAUUUGGGGAGUUUUCAGCCAUUAUUUCUUCAAAUAUUCUUUCUGUGCCUUCCUCUCCUUUCAUUGUGGAACUCCUAUUAUGCAUAUAUUGGCAUAAUUAAUGGUGUCCUACCAGUUUCUUAGACUACUCAUUUUCCUUCAUUUCUUUUUCUUUCUGCUCCUCAGAUUGGGUAAUCUCAAGUGACCUAUCUUCAAGUUUGCUGAUUCCUUCUGCUGUUGAGCCCUUCUAGUGAAAUUUUCUUUUAAGUUAUUAUACUUCUCAACUCCAGAAUUUCUGUUUGGCUCCCUUUAAAAAGUCAUUUUGAUCUAUUUGUUGAUCUUCUCUGUUUGGUAAGACAUCAUUCUCAUGAUUUCCUUUAGUUCUUUGUGCACGAUUCCCUUUAGCUCUUUGAGUGUAUUUAACAUGGUUGAUUAAAAAUCUUUGAUUAGUACAUCCAAUGUGUGGGUUUCCUCAGGCAGUUUUUACUAGUUGCCUUUUUUCCUGUGUAUGGGCAAUACUUCAUCCCUUUGCAUACCAUGUAGUUUUGUUGAAAACUGUAAUUUUUAAUAUUAUAAUGUGGCAACUCUGGAAAUGAGAUUUCCCCCACUCCCCAGGGUUUGUUGCUGCUUAUUGUAGUUGUUGUUUUUGAUUUGGUUAGUGACAUUUCUAUACUAAUUUUAUAAAGUCUAUAUUCUUUAUCAUAUAUGUCCAUUGAAGCUUCUGUUCCAUUAGCUUAGCAGUCAGUUAGUGAUUGACAGAAAUUUCCUCAAACACCUGGGACAAAAUACCAGAAACAACUCUAGUCUUUGUACUUGGCUUCUGUGUAUAUGUCGAAACAUAUUUUAAUACUGAACCAGCAGUUUACAACUCUGUCUUAGCCUUCACUUCCUAUUUGCACAGACCCUGGAGGUCAGCCAGAGGUGAGAGUUUAGGGGUAUCUCAGGUCUUUCCUGAGCAUGCACUCGGCCCUAGCAAGUUAACCUUUUCUAUAUCCUACAGUCACUCUCUGUUGGACUAUACCAGUUAAAGGUCAUUGGCAGAGAAAAUGCAGAGUGAUAGAUUUCUCCUUUCACUCUAUAAGGGCCACUGCCCUGUUUCCAGCAGCACCAUGGAGGGUAGUUUACCAGCAUUGUUCAGUAUAAGUCAGUGAUUGCAAAUAACCACGAUAGUCUUAAAGCAAUGAUUUUUACUAGGUAUUAGAGUAUACCUCUAGGUCAGGAUUUUAGAUUUUAUUCAGCUUGAUUCCAUGUGUAUGGAAUUUAAAUCUACAGAAUACAAGUUUGUUUGUUUUUUUUUUGAGAUGGAGUCUCGCUCUGUCACCCAGGCUGGAGUGCAGUGGCACAAUCUCGGCUCACUGCAACCUCUGCCUCACGGGUUCACACCAUUCUCCUGCCUCAGCCUCCCGUGUAGCUGGGACUACAGGUGCCUGCCAUCAUGCCCCGCUAAUUUUUUGUAUUUUUAGUAGAGACAGGGUUUCACCAUGUUAGCCAGGAUGGUCUCAAUCUCCUGACCUCGUGAUCCGCCCACCUCAGCCUCCCAAAGUGCUGGGAUUACAGGCGUGAGCCACCGCGCCCGGCCAGGGUUUUUUUUUUUUUUAAUGUAAAAUGAUUUAGGCCAGUAUGGUUAACCAGCAUGUACACUUAGAAUUCCAAAAUUCUGUUUGCACAUAUAUUUAUCUUAGCCAGUUCAAGUUAUAAACAUGAGCUCUAUUGCUCAUUUUCUUUAUUGCUGCUAUCUAAUGUUUUUAAUUUUUUGAGAUGCAAUUCUCAUACCAUACAAUCUAUUUUUUAAGGGCAUACAAUCCAUUAGUUUUAUUGUAUUUAUAGUUAUGCAACCAUUACCACUAUCUAAUUGCAGAACACUUUCAUGUCUCUUUUCAUACCUUGCCCAAUCACAGUUACUCCCAGUCCCUGGCAACCACUAAAUUACUGUCUCUCUGAAUUUGCCUUCCCUAAACAUUUUAUAUAAAUGGAAUCAUACAAUAUAUGGCCUUUUCCAACUGGCUUCUUUCACUUAGCAUAAUAUUUUAAAGGUUCAUCCAUGUUGCAGCAUGUAUCAAUACUUCAUUCCUUUUUAUGUCUGAAAAAUAUUCCAUUGUAUGGAUAUGCCACAGUUUAUCCAUUCAUCAGUUAAAGAACAUGUGAGUUAUUUCUACCUUUUGGCUAUUAUGGACUAUGCUGCUAUGAUCAUUAGUAUACAAGUUUUUGUGUGGAUGUAUAUUUUAAUUUCUCUUUGGGUAUAUAUCUAGAAGUGGAAUUGAUGGGUUCUAUGGUAACUCUAUAUUUAGUUUUUUGAAAAACUGUGAGAUUGUUUUCUAAAGCAGCCCAAUUUGCUUUUAGGUGACAAGUUCAAGUUCACAAAGAAAAGGAGUGGGCCAUAUUGACUUAUACUUCUAUAAAUGAAAUGUUUCAAAUGCUGACAAUUUGCAAGGAGAAUGUCUGCAUGAAAACAGUUAAAAUUAUUAUUUUUUUUGAUCAGCCUCACCAGAGCUUCUGAGUAUUACUGCCAUGCCCAUCAGAAUUAAGUCUUUUGCUGAUUCUUCAUGAUAAUUGACAUUUCUAUUUAAUCAGCUUUAAGUUGCUCUCAAACAAACAAAAAAAGCCCAUUAUUCAUAAUCAAAUGCUCCAGAAUCAGACAGAUGCAAGGGCUGGCUUUACUACUUCCUAGCAGUGUCACUUUGAGGAAUAAUGCCUUUUCUUGAAGAAAAACUUCAUUUUCCUCCUCUGUAAAGUGGGAUUAACAGUAUCUACCUCUAGAUGUUCCUGUAUUAGAAUGAGGUCAUGUAUGCAAAACAGUUGCCUGGCAUUUCCUAAGUGCUAAAUAAAUGUUAACUAUUGUUAUUAUUAUUACUGUUAUGUCAUUAUUUAAAUGUAAUUUUUUGAAAGAUAAAUAAUGUCUUAAAAUACUCUCUGAAACUACUUAGAGACAAAGCCUAUUUUAAUAUAGUGAUCAGAUUUUUCAUCUAGCAAACAAAAUCAUUUAUAAUCAAAACCUUUUUUUUUUUUGAGACAGAGUCUCCCUCUGUCUCCCACGCUGGAGUGCAGUGGUGCAAUCUUGGCUCACUGCAGGCUCUGCCUCCUGGAUUCACGCCAUUCUCCUGCUUCAGCCUCCCGAGUAGCUGAGACUACAGGCACCCGCCACCAUGGUUGGCUAAUUUUUUGUAUUUUUAGUAGAGACGGUUUCACUGUGUUAGCCAGGAUGGUCUCGGUCUCCUGACCUUGUGAUCCACCUGCCUUGGCCUCCCAAAGUGCUAGGAUUACAGAUGUAAGCCACCGCGCCCGGCCACAUUUUUUUUUAAGGCUAAGGAAGAACGGGAAGUGGGUGGCUGAAAAAAAUCAAUUAAAAAUAUUUAUUUGCUAGUUAUUCAUUUUGUCCUUGAUAUGUAUUUAAUUUAAAGCAAUUUAUUUUUCUUUUCUUUCUUCCCUGAAGCAAAUGUAAUUUGAACACAGACUAAUUUUUUUUAUAGCUAAAGUGAAAUGUUAAACAAAAUCGUCAUCCCUUUUAGCACUACCUUUAAGUUAUUCUUUACGGAAGAACUGGGUAAACCCUUCACAGAAUGUUUGCAAAACACCUGAUGCACAAUAUGGUGUAAACUGUCACAUUUCUCUUUAAUUUUUUAAUAGUGACCAAAGUGAAUAUUUUUCCAGUGAUUGCUCCAUAAUAUUAUGCUACAAAUGUGUUGUAAAUAAAAGAUUGAUAAUAAAAUACAAAAAAAAAUGAAAUAAACAAUAGAAGACAAAUAUGACAAUAGGCAAGAAUGGUUAGCAAACAUUCUGAUCAAACCUUUUUUGUUAGUUUAAAAGGAAUGCAUCAUUGCUUAGUCUUUGUUCUAAAUGAGAUGUCCCAUUAUCUGUAUCUGGGGCAUGAACAAGUUUUUAUGGCUUGGUGGCAUCAGAAGUUUAAGAGCUGGAAGGGACUUUGGUUGUAAAGGUUGGUCUAGCACAGGGUUUCUCAGCCUGGGCACCAUUGACAAUUUUGCAUUGAUAAUUAUUUGUUGUGGGGGCUGUUCUGUGCAUUGUAGGAUGUAGGCUCUACCCACUAGAUGUCAGUAGUGCAGGGUUCCCCCUACCUGCCUGUUUCCCCCGCCCCCACCACACACAAUGAGAACCACUGAUCUGGGGUUUGCCAAAGUGUACACUCCAUGGAGCACCACUCAUGUUGGAGGGGCUGGGAUACUCCAGGAAAAUAUUCUGUUGUCAAAUAAGUUUGGGAAACCCUUAUUUAGACAACAGCAAAAAAUUGUCAGAGCUUUCAAUGUGAUAUCUAAAGUGAAUUGCCAAGAGGCGAACAUGCAGCAUGUUUCAGCUUAUUUGACAGCAGCCCGUUUUUCAAAGGCAGCUUGCAGGAUGGAACAUACUCCCAUUCCUGUGCUCCAACUCUCAUUUUCCAGGUGAGGAAAUUGAGGUCUAGGGAGGUUACAUGACCAGCCAAAGGCUCUGCAUUACCUAAUUUCAUAAUUGCUGUGUGAGCAUGUACUGCAUGCUAGCUCCUAUGUUAGGCACUGGGGAGGCAAUGGUGAUACACAGGAUAGGCAGAUGGACCCAGUAACUACAACACAAUGUGGUUAGUGCUAGGAGGGAGGCCCUCCAAGAGGCUGAGAGAGCAUCUCAGAAUGGGCACUUCAUUCACAUUGAGUAGAUGAGCUGAGUCCAUGUUGUACAUGUUUUAGCUGAGACAUCUGUGGAGGUAGACCAGUUUGGGAGACCAGGCAGUAGAAUGCCUACAGAGGCCGAUUUUGCAUUUCUGUGUAUAAUAAUUGAGGCAAGGGACUGUAUGAGAGUCCUCCAGGGAUGAGAAGCUUAGGGUAGAACCUUGGGGAAAUCCAUGUUUAAGGGUGCACCGAGGAAGAGCAGCCCCAGAUAGAGACCAAGAAGGACAUAGGAGAAAGUACAGAGCCAGGCAAAGGGUGCAGUCUGAUGCUGCAGAGAGGAAGCUGCAACCUGCAGGGUUGAGGGCCUGGGCUCUGGAGCUGAGCUAGAGUUUGAAUCCUAACUGCCUAGCUUGCAGGUUGUGUGAUAUUUGUCACCUGUUGUAUUACUUUGCAAAGGCUCAAUUUAUAAAAGCAGUAUAAUUGUAAAGCCUACUUCAUCUACUUGUUGUGAAGCCUAGCUAAAGUAUGAGAAGUAUGGAGUACCAUGCUUGGCAUAUAAGAAAUGCUUAGUAAAUAUUCGGUGAUGCUAUCCUUAUUAUUAUCAAAUGACAUGAGGACUCAGAAACAUUCAUGAAUUUGCUUCUUGGAGGUUGUGGGUGACCUUGGCAAAAAUCCAUUUCAGCGGAGGGACAGAUGGUUUGAGAGUGAGUGGGAAGUGAAACGUAGAGGCUGUGAGUUUAGAAUUUUCUCAAGGUUAGUUGUGAAUGGGAUUGGGCAGGGGGGUGGUGGUGAUUGCUGCACAAGAGACUUGGAAUUUGAGUGCUGGCUUUGAACGUACACCACAGCCGCAGCAUAGAGAAGAGUAAUUCUGAGCGGUGAGGAUACCUGCGCAGAAAUGAUGAUGAUGAUACUAAGCACAGGAGUGAGAGACAACUAGGAAACCAAGGAUCGUGGGAGAGAGGGGAGGAGGGAAUGGGCUACAGGGAGGAGGAAAGAAACUGCUCUGCACUAGGACUUGUCUCAGAGCCUAUAGAGGCUACCAGAGUUAAGAUUUGUAGGUUCCUGAAAAUGAGAGUUUAGUGGACCAUUUUGACCUUCUCUCCAUAAUGACAACAUAUUUUUAAAUCCUGAAAGGCAAGAAAAGAGGUUUCCCAAAAAGACUUCUGGGAAGGCGGGCAGGAAUCAGAGCUUCCUGGUGAAGUUAUCAGACACUCUGGGAGUUGGCUUGGAAUGCAUACUCAACUCACUUUGCAAUCAUUCUUAACUUUUAGAGAAAGCCUCCCAAAUCUAACUUUAUUGAACAGCAGCCAUUGGCUCUCUUCCUGAUUUCUCUGUGCACAGAUAGAACUUCCAGCAUCUCCUCCUUUUCUGCUGACCGUUGAUGUGCUGUUUUUCUGACCAGGAAUAGCAAACUUUCCUCUUUCCCAGUCUCCUGUACUGGGCAGGAGGAUUUCUCACCAUCUCCAAAUCUUGGAGGCCUGGGGAAGUUGAGUCCUUCUGAAACUUGAAGAAAGGAGAAUUCUCUCUGUAUCCUGACAUAGGAACUAUUUGAGUAUGAAGAAGGUGCUGCAUGCAUACAUUCAAAGGAACUAGUGAAUAGCUGGCAUGCAUUUUGAUACUGUGCUAAUUGGUAGCCCUGAGGUCUUUGGGCUUUGUUUAUAGACUUCUCCCAAGACCCUCCAAGUAAGGCCUGCAUGUUACUUCUCACAGGCUCUCAGAGAGUCUUGGGAAGACAGAGGCCUCUCUUUUAGACAUGGAGAAGUAUCGUGGGAGGUGAGUUGCCCAAGGACACACAAGACUCCUGUGACUUUCAAGUUAGAGUGGUAUUGUGCAGCCAGAAUUCGCCUGGCAUGGCUUCUGUCUCAGAACCUAGAACAGUGCUCUUCUGCAGUAAAGAUUCCUAGUUUAUUCCCUUUUCUCUUAGUAUAAAACAUUUAAUGUGGGUUAGAGUAUGUUUUUUAUUAUUUCUCCAUUUAACUUGAGAAAGCAACCUCAUGGGUUCAUAUUUUUGUUUCCCUCAUUUUAAAGACAGGCGAGAUUUCACGAGUAGAUGAAAGAACACCCAAAUUUGAGGGAGCGUUCCAAGUUCAUAAAUACUUGUGGCUGAGAGAAAACAAUGGCCCUCCCUCAAAUACUGCAGGGAAGAACCAGUAUUGGGAACAGCUGUGUUUGAAAGUCUCCUAAUUGUUAUUUAUUCUAUCUGUAGAUCUAUAGUCCAACCAAUGUAUGAAUAGGACCUUUGCUGAUUAUAUCUCUGUUUUGAUCAGAACUGCUAUAAAUGAAAGAGUUGUAGUGUACUGUUUUCUUAAACUCCUAGGGUUUUACCACAAAUCAGAGUUGUUUCUUGUGAUACAGCCUUCUUCAGCCUCUGUUCGUCUCUAAGAAAUUGAACCUAGAGUAGUAAACAAGUGAUACUUCUGUAAACUCCCUAAGGGAUGACUCCUCAGUUCUGUGAACCCCAUCAUCCCUCCUAAUCUCAAGUCGCUUAUUUUCUUAUGCUUUGUGGAGCUCUCCUACAAGCACCUGAACUCCAGCAUGUCCCAAAUGUUAUUCAUGAUUUUCUCCUUAAGUCUGCUGCUCCUGCAUGAGUUCCUAUGUCCAUUAAUGACAUUCUUUAUGACACAAGCAAGAAAUCUUGGCACCAUCUUUAUCUCCCGUUUUGCUAACUCCCGUGUACAUUUGACUACUCCAUUUUCCAAGAUGAUAUUCUAGGCAUGUCAGUCUUCUAUUUUUUCCUCUGUAAAGGCAGGUAGUAGGGUAGGAUCCAUAUCUGUAACUCCAAUGCCUUCUGCUUGGAAGAUAAUGCUUCCUGCUGGCCAGUUCCCAUUCCUCAGCCCAAAUACUACAUCCUUGGCAAGCCAUUCCUCUCUGAACCUCCUUCCCAGGAAGAUGCAUUCACUUCUUCCUCUGGAUUGCCAUUUAUUUUUUUUUUUAACUCUAAUGCUCAUGAAACUUUGUGGUAAAAUUUUAUUUGAAGGUCUGGCUCUUCUGCUACAUUCUGAGAUCUUUGAGAGUAGGAACCCAGAUUGUACUUAGAUCCGUGUCUGGCACAUAUGUAAGCACAAAAGCUAUUGACUAUAUUUAAGUGACUUGAAUUAGAAAAAGAUGUAUGAAAUAGAAGAGGAACAAUUAAAUGCUUAUUUGUAUUUGAUCUCAUUUUAGUCUUUUUCUCUUCCCAUUUCAUUCUCUCCUCUCCCUUAGAAAAAAAGCACGUAAAUGUUCUGUUCCUAUAAAAACAAUUUAAAUAGAGACUUUCUUUAUCAGCAGACAGAAUAACCUGGUUGCAUUGUCAAUGUUCUGUCUAAAUGAAGUUUAACUAACAACUGUUGCCUUUAAGGGAUAGAAAAGAAAACCUCACAAAUAUUAUUUAUAGAGAACAUGCAUUGGUCUUAGAGUCUGAGGGUCCAGGUUCCAGUUCGGUUGCUGCCAUUUAUUACGUGAAUGACCCCAGGCAAGUCUCUUUUUUUAAGGUUCAGUUUUCUCCCUUGCAAUGAGAAUAACACCUCCCUGACAAGGUUAUUUUAAGAACUUGAUGAGAUGUUGGAUAUGAAAGCAUCUUGUAUAGGUAAGACACUAAGUUCUGACAUAGAAUAAACUUAUGAUUGCAUGUUUGUAUCCCUGCAAAAUUCAUACAUUGAGAUACAAUCCCCAGUGUGAUGAUUUGAGAUAAUUAGGUCAUGAAGGAGGAGCCCUCAUGAAUGGGAUUAGUGCCCUUAUAAGAAGAGGCCAGAGAGCUAGCUCACUGUCUUUCUGCCAUGUGAAGAUAUAAGGAAAAGGUGGCCAUCUGCAGCCUGGAGAGGGCCCUCACCAGAACCCGACCACACUGGCACCCUGAUCUCACACUUCCAGCCUUCAGAACUGUGAGAAACAAAUUUAUGUUGUUUUAAGCUACCAGUCUAUGGUAAUUCGUUAUGGCUGCCAGAAUUAGGAUAGCUCUUAAUUUUUAGUUGAAUCUGAAUUUAUAUGUAUUUCUUAGGCCUGGAUUUGAAAACCAUUCUGCUAUGUGGUUUAGGUAGUAUCAGCUGUUAGCAUACGCAUUGUCUCAAGGACUAACUUUUCAAUAUCUAUCUUUAUUUCAGGUUAGUAACAUCCUUUGUUUGGGAAUAACAUGCAUAUUAUUUCAUCUGAUGUUUUCCUAAGACAAUUAGAUUGAAUUUUUUUCUUCUCACUUAAGCAUUUUGGAGUACCAUUAGUCCUCUUCCAUGUCUUAGAUAAUAUUGAAUUCAGGGUGUACUUUUAAAAAUCUUGGUAGUUAAAUUUAGCAGUUUUGUUUGGAGGUAUUUAUUUUCAUCUUGGUAAUAAGACAAGAAGUAAGAUGUUUCAUAAUUACCAUAUUUUGUUUGGGAUUUCUGCUGAAUUUUCUCUCUCUCCAUUGCAGUUCUCUUUUUGGAGAGGUCCUUCUCUCUACAGCCAUAUGCUGGUAGAUAAUGCACGGUAGCUGAUCAGUGCUAGAAAAUACAGGAGAUCCAGAGCAUAUUACUCCCUUGAACGUAUCUUUUAGCUGCAGGGAAAACAGAUCUAAGGCAUGAAUUACAACUUAUUAGUUGUAGAUGGACUCUGUAGCCCAGUACUGAUUAAGAAGAAACAGCCUCACUCUGUCUUGCCAUGAUGGCUGUUCCAAGUCAAAGGAAAAGGAGAAGUCUGUUGGAGAAGAUUUUCUUUCUUUUUUCCUUCUUCUUCUUUUCUUUAGUUCAUCCAUUCAUUUAUUUUCUAAUAUUAUGGGACACAAAAGCAGAAUUUGUAGUUAGUACUCUUGGCUGUAGAAAUUCGUAGUUUUGCUUUUCCUUUAAGGUUGAUUCCAGCACCACUUUGUGAGAAGAAACUGUCAUAGUUUCACAUUGCCUCUAAGAAAAUGAAACGUACCUAAGUAUUAUUGGACAGCCGGAGUAUUUUACAGUGGUUGCUGCUCAGGAAAUUUGAGUGAAGGACUGCAAAAGAGGAGCAAAGCAGACCCGAGAGAGAAGGCAGCAGUGCUCCCCUGUGACGUGCUCCAUCACCGGGCAGGGAAGACACCGCUGCCACCUCUCCACAGCCUUGUUCAAGAGCACUGGAAAUUGUAAGGUGUUUGUUUUGUUUCAUUUUGGGAGUGGUGGAAGAUUAGCCUUUGUGUUUCUCCUCUAAAGAGUUUUGUCUAAAACGCUUACGACUACUUAGUUAAACAAAAAUCCAAAGUAAGCUAUCAUUGAAAUAUGAAAUAUACUAACAAAGCCAAACAGUAAAAGAUUAUACAGGGAAAGUCCUUUCUCCCCAUUUUGACUUCACCCACUCAGUUUCCCUUCCCAGUGUCCUUCCAGAGAGAUAUUUGACUCAUGAAUCAGCACAUAUAUUCAUAUGCCUGCUUUUUCAUACACUGUAGCAGCAUACUAGAAUAUUGUUCAGCAUUUUUAUUUCUUUUUUUUUUAACCUUACACUAUUUCCUGAUGUUUUCCAAGUAAAUGUUUUAUUUUUUUUCUUAUGGUUGUGUAGUAUACAUCCAUUGUGUAGAUGGAUGUGUAAAGUACACAUCCAUUGUAUAGAUGUGUAAUUUAUUUAGCCAGUUUCUUGAGGAAUAUUUAGGUGUGGUGGCUCAUGUCUGUAAUCCCAGCUCUCUUGGAGGCUGAGGGGGGCAGAUCACCUGAGGUCAGGAGUUCGAGACCAGCUUGGCCAACAUGGUGAAACCUGUCUCUACUAAAAAUACAGAAAUUAGCCGGGCAUGAUGGUGGGUGCCUGUAAUCCCAGCUACUCAGGAGGCGGAGGCAGGAGAAUCGCUUGAACCCAGGAGGCGGAGGUUGCAGUGAGCCCAGAUUGCACCACUGCACUCCAGCCUGAACGACAGAGUGAGACUGUCUCAAAAACAAACGAACAAAAAAGUCUUGGUGUAUGAAUAAGGAAAGGAGCCCUAGAUAUUGGGCAUGCAAAGGCUUUUGUGUUCUCUGAAAAGGUCAUGCAAUGAUAGAAGUGACCCGAGACACCUGUAAACUGAUGACCCACAGUUAAAUCCACAUAAUGUGGCCAGUGCUGUGGUUUUGGGUAAGUGCAGGAUGCUGUGGACAGUGGGUGCCUAAGAGCUACAUUUCACUCAAGUGCUGGAGAAGCAGGAGAGAUUGACCCUAAGGAAGUUCCUGCUAAGCUGAGCCCUGGAGAAUGUGAGGAACAUAGGUUAGGAAAGGGUAGAAUAGUGUGAGGAACUGUGUUCUAGGAGAGGGAACACCAGCAUGCCCAGAGAUCAUCAUGGCCCGUUUGAGCUUCAGAAGUGUAUCUGUUGGCAGUCUGGAGAGGAGACUGGCAAGGUAAUCAGGCAUUGGAAUCACCGUAGCUCUCCAUAAGUGUCAAGGAGGUUGGACAUAAGGCUAUGGGAGGCCAGUGAAGACCUUUAUCAGGAGUGGGAGGUUAUUUGAUUUGUGUUUAAAAAUCUCAUCCUGCCUGCCAGGUGGAGAGUAAACCGGAAAGGGAUGGGAUGCUAUGUAGGAAGCUGUUGCAGUAAUCCAAGUGAAAGGUGAUGGUGGCCUGAACUAGGAAAUGGCAGUGCAACUAGGAAGAAGUAGACACAGAAGAGCUCUUCAGACAGUGGAAUCAACAGGAGUUAGCAAUUUUGAGACGUGGGCAUGGAGGCAGAGACCCUCAGCCCUCUGGUUGUUCACUUUUAACAAAAAGAUUAUGUGCAAUGCAUUUAACAUAUUAUUCUUGCAUCUUUAUGAAACCAUCCUCAUUAUUUCUUUUGGACAAAUCCUGGAAGUAGACUUGCUGAGUCAAAGGAAAGAUCUUGAAAUAUUUCAAUAAUGUAGUCAAAUUGCCUCCAGAAAGGCUAAUACGCCAAUUGUCCAUUACCAAUUAGGGCACUAGCUUCAGCCUCACUGAGUAUUAUCGCUUUGAAUUGACACCAAUCUGAUAGGAAGAAAAUACAUACCUUUUCUUUAUUUUAAUUUGCAUUUCUGUGAGUACUGGCAAAGUUGAAGUUUUUUUCAUGCUUAUCAACUAAUUAUAUUUCCACAAAUUACAUAUUCAUAUCUUUGCUUAUUUUCCCCCUGAGGUGUUUAUCUUUGUCUUUUUUAUUUCUAAGAGCUCUAUUACUCUUUAGUUGCUUAACCCUUUGUCUUUUCUAUUUGUUGCAGGAUUUCUCUCAUUUAUUUAUGCUUUUGUUUAUAUUUUGUUGAUCAGAAAGUUUUUUAAUGUAAUAAAAUAUUUUGUUCAUGCUUUAUGCCUGUAGUUCAGUGUGAAGAAAAUUCUUCCUCAACCCCAGGUUGAGGUAUAAAUAGUGGGAUUUUUAUAAAUAUUCACAUUUAUUUUCAUUUUUUACCUUCGGGUCUUUAAUUCAUCCGGAAUUUUCGGAUAUGUGUUGUAGGAAUCUAUCUCUUUUUGAUCGGAAUAAUAAUUUUUUUUUCUGAACCAAAAAUCGGGACAACCUAGUCUAUGUAACAAAUAAUUUUUAUGCAUUUGUGUGGCAGAAGCAGUUUUAGAGAGUAAUAAUAUUGGAAUUUCUGGGACAUUUGAUGUUAUAUAUGUUGAUAGAUUAUAGAGAGAUAAGAUUUAAGGACUAAUACUUAUACCUGGGCAACAUCAGGGAACCUGUGCCAUUGCUAAAAAAUAAAAAAAGAAAGAAUGGCUCCCAACACCCAUUCAGAAUAGAAUGUUUGAAAUCCAGAGUGCAUGAGAAAGUUCAGGAUCCAGAUUGUAAAAUAUUGCCAAUGGUUUAUGUAGUGCAACCUGCAUUUCACUGAUAGCUCAUGUUAUCCUUCCUAUUUGAAACACUAGUUAACAUCAAAAUGACUUUUCAGGUCCGUGGUGGCUCUAAUCUUUGUAUGUUGGUAGGUUCCUUUCUAGGCAGAACAUCCAAAGACAACCCAUUCUCUUGAGGCCAUCAGAACAAGAUCAAAGGUUGUAGAGCCUUGACCACAGUAUUAAAGCAAAGCCUCAAAAUGACUUAAGGAAUCUUAGGAAAUAAAAUGCCACAGUCCUGGACAUUUAUCAUUUGGCAGCAAGCUAAACAUUUCCUAAAACUUUUACAAGUAAUUUAGGUACCUAAUGGAAAUUUUUUGUUUUUAAAUUCUGGAGUUGCCUAAAUUGUUUAGGAGAAAUUUAGCUGGAAUCUGGCGAUAGGACUGUUUAUAUGUGCUUGGCUCAGGGUGGCUGUGUUGUCCACAUUAGCAUGACCAUGGGCUCCUUAUCGAAGCCCUGGUUCCCAGUAAGUGCUGUUUGCAAGAGUGAGGUGGAGUUUGGUGGCUUUCAGGCCACCCAGAGUGCCAUGUGUAUCUGUUUGAUAAACUCUGUGGUUUGUCUGUUCUCUGUGUUUUUGCCAGAUUGUUUAAAAAAAAAAGAAAGAAAGAAAAAGCAAACAAGCAGGCAUCAUAUGUUAAAAGUUUAUCUUUCUACAUGAAUUUUUGGAAAAUCUAAGUGUAAUUUUAUUCCUGAAAGAACAAAAAGUUGUUUCCCUGGGGAGAUAAUUUUGGGGUGCAUAGAUAUUUUUAAGGCUGUAGAUAUUAACUAUGAAAAUAAUAUAUAACUUUGUCAAUACUUUUUUUUCAGCAGGCUAAGCCAUAUUUUUUCAAAAAAACGAGGCUGGAAUCAACUACUCUUGGCAUAUCAGAGAUCAGGAAAAAAUGGGUAUUGGAAGCCAUUCUUUUUUUUCUUCAUGACAGCACAGGCUUUCUGAUGUUGUCCAGGUGUUGUGCUGGCCGCAUAAGAUUUGCUGUUGCGGCUUUCUAUGGAUGGUUGACCAAUUCAGAUGAAGCACCCACCUGCUGUGGAAAAUCUGGAAAAUCAGCCAAAGAUGGUACAAAACAGAAGAGGGAACGGAAAAAGACAGUCUCAUUCAGCAGCAUGCCAACAGAGAAGAAGAUCAGCAGUGCAAGUGAUUGUAUUAAUUCAAUGGUUGAGGGUUCAGAACUCAAAAAGGUUCGCUCCAACUCUAGAAUUUAUCAUAGGUACUUUUUACUGGAUGCUGACAUGCAGAGCCUAAGGUGGGAGCCAUCUAAGAAGGAUUCUGAGAAAGCCAAGAUUGACAUUAAAUCCAUCAAGGAAGUGAGAACAGGAAAAAACACAGACAUAUUCCGCAGCAAUGGCAUUUCUGACCAGAUAUCUGAAGAUUGUGCGUUUUCCGUCAUAUAUGGAGAGAAUUAUGAGUCACUGGAUUUGGUUGCCAACUCCGCAGAUGUUGCAAACAUCUGGGUUACAGGACUGCGGUACCUAAUUUCUUAUGGAAAACAUACACUUGAUAUGUUAGAAAGUAGCCAAGAUAACAUGAGGACUUCUUGGGUUUCACAAAUGUUUAGUGAAAUUGAUGUAGAUAACCUUGGACAUAUAACUCUGUGUAAUGCUGUGCAAUGUAUCAGAAACCUCAAUCCUGGUUUAAAAACGAGCAAAAUUGAGCUUAAGUUCAAAGAAUUGCAUAAAUCAAAGGACAAAGCUGGUACCGAGGUCACAAAGGAAGAAUUUAUUGAGGUUUUUCAUGAGCUUUGUACUAGACCUGAAAUUUAUUUCCUUUUAGUUCAGUUUUCAAGCAAUAAAGAAUUCCUUGAUACCAAGGACCUUAUGAUGUUUCUUGAGGCAGAACAGGGUGUGGCACAUAUAAAUGAGGAAAUAAGCCUUGAAAUUAUUCACAAAUAUGAACCAUCCAAAGAGGGUCAGGAAAAGGGCUGGCUCUCCAUAGACGGGUUCACUAAUUACCUUAUGUCACCUGACUGUUAUAUAUUCGAUCCAGAACAUAAGAAGGUCUGUCAGGAUAUGAAGCAACCUCUGUCUCAUUACUUUAUAAACUCAUCUCAUAAUACAUACUUAAUAGAGGAUCAGUUCCGAGGUCCCUCCGACAUCACAGGAUAUAUUCGAGCUCUUAAAAUGGGUUGCCGGAGUGUUGAAUUAGAUGUAUGGGAUGGGCCGGACAAUGAACCUGUAAUUUACACAGGCCACACCAUGACCUCUCAGAUAGUUUUCCGCAGUGUCAUUGAUAUUAUUAACAAGUAUGCAUUCUUUGCUUCAGAGUAUCCUCUUAUCUUGUGUUUAGAAAACCACUGUUCCAUUAAACAACAGAAGGUAAUGGUUCAGCACAUGAAGAAACUUUUAGGAGACAAGCUCUAUACAACAUCACCCAAUGUUGAGGAAUCUUAUCUACCAUCCCCAGAUGUCCUGAAAGGGAAAAUACUAAUUAAAGCAAAGAAGCUGUCCUCAAAUUGCUCUGGGGUAGAAGGAGAUGUUACUGACGAAGAUGAAGGAGCAGAAAUGUCUCAGAGGAUGGGAAAAGAGAACAUGGAGCAACCCAAUAAUGUGCCUGUGAAGCGAUUUCAGCUUUGUAAAGAACUGUCUGAACUGGUCAGCAUCUGCAAAUCAGUUCAGUUCAAAGAAUUUCAGGUGUCGUUUCAGGUUCAGAAGUACUGGGAAGUCUGUUCCUUUAAUGAAGUGCUUGCCAGCAAGUACGCCAAUGAAAAUCCAGGGGACUUUGUAAAUUACAACAAACGUUUUCUUGCUAGGGUUUUUCCCAGUCCAAUGAGAAUUGAUUCCAGUAACAUGAAUCCUCAAGAUUUUUGGAAAUGUGGUUGCCAAAUUGUAGCCAUGAACUUUCAGACACCAGGACUGAUGAUGGACCUGAAUAUUGGCUGGUUUAGGCAGAACGGAAACUGUGGCUAUGUCCUCCGGCCAGCCAUCAUGAGGGAGGAGGUCUCCUUCUUCAGCGCCAAUACAAAAGACUCUGUCCCAGGGGUCUCACCUCAACUUCUUCACAUUAAAAUCAUCAGUGGGCAGAACUUUCCCAAGCCCAAAGGAUCAGGUGCCAAAGGUGAUGUGGUAGAUCCUUAUGUCUAUGUUGAAAUCCAUGGAAUCCCUGCUGAUUGUGCAGAACAAAGGACAAAAACAGUGCACCAGAAUGGAGACGCUCCCAUUUUUGAUGAAAGCUUUGAAUUUCAAAUCAACCUGCCUGAACUGGCCAUGGUGCGCUUUGUAGUGCUGGAUGAUGACUACAUUGGGGAUGAAUUCAUCGGCCAGUACACAAUUCCCUUUGAAUGUUUACAGACGGGCUACCGCCAUGUCCCCCUGCAGUCCUUAACUGGAGAGGUCCUUGCACAUGCUUCUUUAUUUGUCCACGUGGCUAUUACUAACCGAAGAGGAGGAGGAAAGCCUCAUAAAAGGGGCCUUUCUGUGAGAAAAGGGAAGAAAUCCAGGGAAUAUGCAUCUUUGAGAACACUGUGGAUUAAAACCGUGGAUGAGGUAUUCAAGAAUGCCCAGCCCCCUAUACGGGAUGCCACAGAUCUGAGAGAAAACAUGCAGAAUGCGGUGGUGUCAUUCAAGGAGCUGUGUGGCCUCUCCUCUGUGGCCAAUCUCAUGCAGUGCAUGUUGGCGGUGUCUCCCCGCUUUCUGGGGCCCGAUAACACACCCCUAGUGGUCCUAAAUCUCAGCGAGCAGUACCCCACAAUGGAGCUGCAGGGAAUUGUGCCGGAGGUUCUGAAGAAGAUCGUAACAACUUAUGACAUGAUGAUUCAGUCCCUCAAGGCGUUGAUUGAAAAUGCAGAUGCUGUAUAUGAAAAGAUCGUACAUUGUCAGAAGGCAGCCAUGGAAUUCCAUGAACACUUGCACAGCAUAGGCACCAAGGAAGGUUUGAAGGAAAGAAAACUACAAAAAGCAGUGGAGAGCUUUACCUGGAAUAUUACCAUCUUAAAGGGACAAGCAGAUCUUUUGAAAUAUGCUAAGAAUGAGACAUUGGAGAACCUGAAACAAAUCCAUUUUGCUGCUGUUUCAUGUGGACUGAAUAAACCAGGCACCGAAAAUGCUGAUGUCCAGAAGCCACGCCGGAGCUUGGAAGUCAUACCCGAAAAAGCAAACGAUGAAACUGGAGAAUGAGGAAACUUACAAUAAACCAUUAUGGAGUUUAUAACUCUAGGACCAAUUGUAGUCAGAUGGGACAUUUGCUUUGCACUCACUAAUGAGAAUAAUAUUCGGGAUUUUAAAGCACAACUGGAAUAGCUAAUUACAGUCUAUUAAAACUGUGAAUGUAUGUAGCAAUCCUGCGUGUGAAGGCAAAUAAACUCUUUAACAGGCAAUUAUAUUGCUGGCCAAAAUAUGCUAUAUUUGUAUACAAAGACAUUCUAACUCAGUUCCAGUAUGAAGAAAGAUUAUUCACUCUAGCUCCACUGAGAAACAUUUUCCUAAGUGAAAACAAUUUCUUAAGAUGGAAAUGGAUUGGAUUGUCAAAUUAUUAUUUAUUGGAGAAAAAAACCUGAUCUACACAUUUUUACUUAUAUGGGGUUGCCAGAGUCUCUGGGUUCUAGAUGAUUUUGGUGGCAUGCUUGCUGAGCCAUAAUUACUAAAGAGAAUGUAAGUGGACGGGUUCCCUGAAUCCCCGGGGUCCUUGGAGAGCCAUCGAGGAGAAUGUGCAAUUGGACUGAAGCUCCCUGGCUGAAGAUACAUGCCGAGUCAGCACAUGGGUAGAGAUGAUGUAAAAGCAGCCAAUCUGGAAACAAUACAUUGUAAAUAGUUUUUCAUUGUAUGAAGUAGUGUUCACAUUAAAAAGAUGUUUUAUGAUAUUUCUCCAAUA